AUCCAUUGAGGAGCUGCCUCGCGCAGGGGGUGUGCGAGGCUGAGUCCAAGAGAUAGCAAAUCGAGUCUUAAAUAAUCCGGGGAGAAAGACGCCCGGGUAGAUUUGAGGUGCAGCCUUGGAGGGAGGGAUUAGAAGCCGCUAGACUUUUUUUCCUCCCCUCUCAGUAGCACGGAGUCCGAAUUAAUUGGAUUUCAUUCACUGGGGAGGAACAAAAACUAUCUGGGCAGCUUCAUUGAGAGAGAUUCAUUGACACUAAGAGCCAGCGGCUGCAGCUGGGUGCAGAGAGAACCUCCGGCUUUACUUCUGUCUCGUCUGCCCCAACCGCUAGCCUCGGCUUGGGUAAGGCGAGGCGGAAUUAAACCCCGCUCCGAGAGCGGCAGCUUCGCGCGCGGUGCGCUCGGCCUAUGCCUGCCCCGAGGGGCGUCUGGUAGGCACCCCGCCCUCUCCCGCAGCUCGACCCCCAUGAUAGAUACGCUCAGACCCGUGCCCUUCGCGUCGGAAAUGGCGAUCAGCAAGACGGUGGCGUGGCUCAACGAGCAGCUGGAGCUGGGCAACGAGCGGCUGCUGCUGAUGGACUGCCGGCCGCAGGAGCUAUACGAGUCGUCGCACAUCGAGUCGGCCAUCAACGUGGCCAUCCCGGGCAUCAUGCUGCGGCGCCUGCAGAAGGGUAACCUGCCGGUGCGCGCGCUCUUCACGCGCGGCGAGGACCGGGACCGCUUCACCCGGCGCUGUGGCACCGACACAGUGGUGCUCUACGACGAGAGCAGCAGCGACUGGAACGAGAAUACGGGCGGCGAGUCGGUGCUCGGGCUGCUGCUCAAGAAGCUCAAGGACGAGGGCUGCCGGGCGUUCUACCUGGAAGGUGGCUUCAGUAAGUUCCAAGCCGAGUUCUCCCUGCAUUGCGAGACCAAUCUAGACGGCUCGUGUAGCAGCAGCUCGCCGCCGUUGCCAGUGCUGGGGCUCGGGGGCCUGCGGAUCAGCUCUGACUCUUCCUCGGACAUCGAGUCUGACCUUGACCGAGACCCCAAUAGUGCAACAGACUCGGAUGGUAGUCCGCUGUCCAACAGCCAGCCUUCCUUCCCAGUGGAGAUCUUGCCCUUCCUCUACUUGGGCUGUGCCAAAGACUCCACCAACUUGGACGUGUUGGAGGAAUUCGGCAUCAAGUACAUCUUGAACGUCACCCCCAAUUUGCCGAAUCUCUUUGAGAACGCAGGAGAGUUUAAAUACAAGCAAAUCCCCAUCUCGGAUCACUGGAGCCAAAACCUGUCCCAGUUUUUCCCUGAGGCCAUUUCUUUCAUAGAUGAAGCCCGGGGCAAGAACUGUGGUGUCUUGGUACAUUGCUUGGCUGGCAUUAGCCGCUCAGUCACUGUGACUGUGGCUUACCUUAUGCAGAAGCUCAAUCUGUCGAUGAACGAUGCCUAUGACAUUGUCAAAAUGAAAAAAUCCAACAUAUCCCCUAACUUCAACUUCAUGGGUCAGCUGCUGGACUUCGAGAGGACGCUGGGACUCAGCAGCCCAUGUGACAACAGGGUUCCAGCACAGCAGCUGUAUUUUACCACCCCUUCCAACCAGAAUGUAUACCAGGUGGACUCUCUGCAAUCUACGUGAAAGACCCCACACCCCUCCUUGCUGGAAUGUGUCUGGCCCUUCAGCAGUUUCUCUUGGCAGCAUCAGCUGGGCUGCUUUCUUUGUGUGUGGCCCCAGGUGUCAAAAUGACACCAGCUGUCUGUACUAGACAAGGUUACCAAGUGCGGAAUUGGUUAAUACUAACAGAGAGAUUUGCUCCAUUCUCUUUGGAAUAACAGGACAUGCUGUAUAGAUACAGGCAGUAGGUUUGCUCUGUACCCAUGUGUACAGCCUACCCAUGCAGGGACUGGGAUUCGAGGACUUCCAGGCGCAUAGGGUAGAACCAAAUGAUAGGGUAGGAGCAUGUGUUCUUUAGGGCCUUGUAAGGCUGUUUCCUUUUGCAUCUGGAACUGACUAUAUAAUUGUCUUCAAUGAAGACUAAUUCAAUUUUGCAUAUAGAGGAGCCAAAGAGAGAUUUCAGCUCUGUAUUUGUGGUAUCAGUUUGGAAAAAAAAAUCUGAUACUCCAUUUGAUUAUUGUAAAUAUUUGAUCUUGAAUCACUUGACAGUGUUUGUUUGAAUUGUGUUUGUUUUUUCCUUUGAUGGGCUUAAAAGAAAUUAUCCAAAGGGAGAAAGAGCAGUAUGCCACUUCUUAAAACAGAACAAAACAAAAAAAGAAAAUUGUGCUCUUUUCUAAUCCAAAGGGUAUAUUUGCAGCAUGCUUGACUUUACCAAUUCUGAUGACAUCUUUACGGACACUAUUAUCACUAAGACCUUGUUAUGGCGAAGUCUUUAGUCUUUUUCAUGUAUUUUCCUCAUGAUUUUUUCUCUUUAUGUAGUUUGACUAUGCCUUACCUUUGUAAAUAUUUUUGCUUGUGUUGUCGCAAAGGGGAUAAUCUGGGAAAGACACCAAAUCAUGGGCUCACUUUAAAAAAAGAAAGAAUAAAAAAACCUUCAGCUGUGCUAAACAGUAUAUUACCUCUGUAUAAAAUUCUUCAGGGAGUGUCACCUCAAAUGCAAUACUUUGGGUUGGUUUCUUUCCUUUAAAAAAAUUUGUAUAAAACUGGAAGUGUGUGUGUGUGAGCAUGGGUACCCAUUUGAUAAGAGAAAUGCAUUUGAUUGUGAAGAAGGGAGAGUUAAAUUCUCCAUUAUGUUCGUGGUGUAAAGUUUAGAGCUGGAAUUUAUUAUAAGAAUGUAAAACCUUAAAUUAUUAAUAAAUAACUAUUUUGGCUAUUGAAUGUGUGUUUUUAAAAACUCAGUUAUACCUAUGUGUGAAGUGACACAUUUUAGAACUUUUUCAUUCAGGGAUUGAUUUUGACUUGUAGGCAUAGUAGGGCAAGGUUCUUUUAAGCUUUUCCUAGAACGUUUUUCAGCAGCAGUUUAUGAAAUUCAUCGUUUGCCACGAAUAAAGAUGACAUCCUAGAAUGGACCGACUGUACCGUGUAUAUGAACAAUACCUCUUAUGAGUAUAGUUCCGGCUUAAGAUUUUAAAGCCCCUGAAGAAAAAUGAACCUAUAGAGCAUAGCUUGCUGAGGAAUACAAUUUGGAUAUUAACCACAGAGAGGUGUAGCAGAAUACCAAGAUGACAGCCACAUGUUAACCUCCUCCCUAUCCUUCACUGUCAGGAUCUUCUGCUUUAUAAUGCUGAGAUAAUGCCAAAGAGGAAGUAGGGAUAAUUCUUUUUCCAGUCUGUUGUCAUGGGCAAUUCUACCUGCAGAUAUCCUAGUGUGAGAAUGCUGAAUCCAGAAUGAUGUCUCCACUUUUUCCCCUAGCAUGCGCAUGGCAAGGCAUAUCUAAGCUUCCUCACCGUGUCAGGAUAUGGCUUUAGAAUUUUACAUUGGCACUUAGGAGGCAACUUUGUCAUCCCUGUUGUAAUGUGCUUUUUUGUUUAACUGGCUUGGGAUGUGGGUCAGAAACCCUUAUUGAAACUUGUGGGGAUUAUUUUAGUUUCUUUUCAAGCUAAAGACUUUAUAUCUUGCCAUUUUUCUUGGGACCUACCCUCUCCUUACCUCAAAUGUAAAAAUACACAAACCAAAAUAAAAGGCAGGUGUAUGGAAUCAAAA